GUAGAAGGGCAACCUCGUGCUUUCUGCAGAGGAGACCGGAGGGCAGAAGGCAGAGUCCAGGCUUAGACUGCAGUUCCUCGCUUACCUGUGCAGUCUAAUUUUGAGCUGCCUCUUUGUAGUCUUAAAAGGCAGGAGCUUCGUGUUGUGGGUCUGCUAACCCGUACGUUUCCGUGGGCAAGUCGUGUGUACUCCUCGCCAUGGCUCAGCUCCAAACACGCUUCUACACUGAUAACAAGAAAUAUGCCGUAGAUGAUGUUCCCUUCUCAAUCCCUGCUGCCUCUGAAAUUGCCGACCUUAGUAACAUCAUCAAUAAACUACUAAAGGACAAAAAUGAGUUCCACAAACAUGUGGAGUUUGAUUUCCUUAUUAAGGGCCAGUUUCUGCGAAUGCCCUUGGACAAACACAUGGAAAUGGAGAACAUCUCAUCAGAAGAAGUUGUGGAAAUAGAAUACGUGGAGAAGUAUACUGCACCCCAGCCAGAGCAAUGCAUGUUCCAUGAUGACUGGAUCAGUUCAAUUAAAGGGGCAGAGGAAUGGAUCUUGACUGGUUCUUAUGAUAAGACUUCUCGGAUCUGGUCCUUGGAAGGAAAGUCAAUAAUGACAAUUGUGGGACAUACGGAUGUUGUAAAAGAUGUGGCCUGGGUGAAAAAAGAUAGUUUGUCCUGCUUAUUAUUGAGUGCUUCUAUGGAUCAGACUAUUCUCUUAUGGGAGUGGAAUGUAGAGAGAAACAAAGUGAAAGCCCUACACUGCUGUAGAGGUCAUGCUGGAAGUGUAGAUUCUAUAGCUGUUGAUGGCUCAGGAACUAAAUUUUGCAGUGGCUCCUGGGAUAAGAUGCUAAAGAUCUGGUCUACAGUCCCUACAGAUGAAGAAGAUGAAAUGGAGGAGUCCACAAAUCGACCAAGAAAGAAACAGAAGACAGAACAGUUGGGACUAACAAGGACUCCCAUAGUGACCCUCUCUGGCCACAUGGAGGCAGUUUCCUCAGUUCUGUGGUCAGAUGCUGAAGAAAUCUGCAGUGCAUCUUGGGACCAUACAAUUAGAGUGUGGGAUGUUGAGUCUGGCAGUCUUAAGUCAACUUUGACAGGAAAUAAAGUGUUUAAUUGUAUUUCCUAUUCUCCACUUUGUAAACGUUUAGCAUCUGGAAGCACAGAUAGGCAUAUCAGACUGUGGGAUCCCCGAACUAAAGAUGGUUCUUUGGUGUCGCUGUCCCUAACGUCACAUACUGGUUGGGUGACAUCAGUAAAAUGGUCUCCUACCCAUGAACAGCAGCUGAUUUCAGGAUCUUUAGAUAACAUUGUUAAGCUGUGGGAUACAAGAAGUUGUAAGGCUCCUCUCUAUGAUCUGGCUGCUCAUGAAGACAAAGUUCUGAGUGUAGACUGGACAGACACAGGGCUACUUCUGAGUGGAGGAGCAGACAAUAAAUUGUAUUCCUACAGAUAUUCACCUACCACUUCCCAUGUUGGGGCAUGAAAGUGAACAAUAAUUUGACUAUAGAGAUUAUUUCUGUAAAUGAAAUUGGUAGAGAACCAUGAAAUUACAUAGAUGCAGAUGCAGAAAGCAGCCUUUUGAAGUUUAUAUAAUGUUUUCACCCUUCAUAACAGCUAACGUAUCACUUUUUCUUAUUUUGUAUUUAUAAUAAGAUAGGUUGUGUUUAUAAAAUACAAACUGUGGCAUACAUUCUCUAUACAAACUUGAAAUUAAACUGAGUUUUACAUUUCUCUUUAAAGGUAUUGGUUUGAAUUCAGAUUUGCUUUUUUAUUUUUAUUUGUUUUUUUUUUUUUUGAGAUGGAGUCUUGCUCUGUUGCCUAGGCUGGAGUGCAGUGGCGCAAUCUCAACUCACUGCAACCUCCGCUUCCUAGGUUCAAUCGAUUCUCCUGUCUCAACCUCCCAAGUAGCUGGGAUUACAGGCACACAUCACGAUGUCCUGCUAAUUUUUGUAUUUUUAGUAGAGACGGGGUUUUGCCAUGUUGGCCAGGCUGGUCUUGAACUCCUGACCUCAGGUGAUCUGCCCACCUCAGCCUCCCAAAGUGAGCCACUGUGCCUGGCCGAAUUAAGAUUUGUUUUUGAAAUGCUGUAAAAGGUUAUAUUGGAAAUCCAGUAAUUGAUUGUUGAGAUUUUUAUUUCUGUUAGAGACUUAGAUUUUUUUAAGUUAGCUAUUUUAAAAAAGCAUUCAAAAAGAUUAAUGAAAAUUGUAAUAGAGAAAAAGUUAGAAAUUCAGUUCCUUUUGGCAGAAUAAAUGUUCAAGAAAAUUAGGCUGUGAGGGUACUCAGAACAUUAAAAAAAAUGUAGGCUGGGCAUGGUGGCUCACACCUGUAAUCCCAGCACAUUGGGAGGCCGAGGCAGGUGGAUCACCUGAGGUCAGGAGUUUGAGACCACCCUGGCCAACAUGUCAAAACCCUGUCUCUGCUAAAACUACAAAAAUUAGCUGGGCAUGGUGGCGACCGCCUGUAAUCCCAACUACUUGGGAGGCUAAGGCAGGAGAAUUGCUUGAACCCGGGAGGCAGGGGUUGUAGUGAGCUGAGAUUGUGCCACUGCACUCCAGCCUGGGUGACAGUGCAAGACUCUGUCUCAACAACAACGAUAACAAAAUAUUGAUUCGGCAGGGCACGGUGGCUCAUGCUUGUAAUCCCAGCAUUUUGGGUGGCCAAGGCAGGCGGCUCACCUGAGGUCAGGGGUUCGAGACCAGCCUGACCAACAUGGUGAAACUUUGUCUCUACUAAAAAAAAAAAAAUCCAAAACAAAUUAGCCGGGUGUGGUGGCACACUCCUGUGGUCCCAAGUACUUGGGAGGCUGAGGCAGGAGAAUUGGUUGAACCCAGGAGGUGGAGGUUGCAGUGAGCUGAGAUCAUACCACUGUGCUCCAGCCUGGGCAGCAGAGCCAGACUCUAUCUCAAAAUAAAGACAAGUAGAUUGCCAAUUUUUGAAGAAUUCAUCAAGAUAUUUUAAGGAAGGCACUUUAUAUUAAAUAUAUGUCAGAUCCUUUAGAAAUUGCAUACAGUUGGUUGGGCACGGUGGCUCACGCCUGUAAUCCCAGCACUUUGGGAGGCUGAGGCGGGCGGAUUGCCUGAGCUCAGGAGUUCGAAACCAGCCUGGGCAACACAGUGAAACCUCGUCUCUAAUAAAAUACAAAAAAUUAGCUGGGCGUGGCAGCAUGUGCCUGUAGUCCCAGCUACUCCGGAGGCUGAGGCAGGCAAAUUGCUUGAACCCGAGAGGCAGAGGUUGCAGUGAGCUGAGAUUGUGCCACUGCAUUUCAGCCUGGGCAACAGAGCAAGACUCUGUCUCAAAAAAAAAUAAAAAAUUGCAUUGCAUACAGUUUUCACUGUAACCCUAAUCUUUCCUCAUGUGUAGAUUAGAAUAAAUUUUUUAGACAAAACCUUUCAUCAGUAUUAAACAUUCUACAGAUUUUAUGAUAUCAUUAGCAUUUAUCUUUAUGCAUGUGUUAUAUAAAAAUAUUUAAAGUAAAUGUAUUUUUUAAAUGUUAUUUCCAUUAUUAAUGGAUUGAUACUCCUUAAGUAGAGCAUUCACAACCUUUUAGUAAUAUUUGGGAAAUAUGUUUGGUCUCAUUAUUAGAUGGUAUUACAUCUCAAAUGAUGUUCCUGUUGCAGAAGUCUGCGAAACAAUAUCUAAACUUGGCUGCAGUUGAGAGCUAAACAGUGUAUUGAACCAGUUAGGAGUUUAGUUCUCUGUAGAAAACCAGAGGCAGUCCAGGGCUGAUGUAGGUUUUGUUCCACAUUCUUUAGGAUCCUAGGCUCCCUCCAUCCCUGGUAUGUGGUCCUCAUUUUCAUAUAGACCAAGAGCUAGAGCUCCAGUUACCAUUUCUUAAAGUAUAUUUUAAUGCCAAAUAGUGAAUAAAGGUGGCCAGAAAAUUCAUGCACAGAAUCCUUCUUUUUCUCAUUUUGUGCUGAUUGGUAUAAAUUUUAUUGUAUUUGUAGUCUCUGGAAAUCUUCUAACUUUGAGAGGACAAAGAUGAAUUCCUAGUCCUGUUUUGGAUGGUCUUCAAAUGAUCCUUAAGGGCAGUUAUUUAAAAUGUCUUUCUUAACUCACCCAACCUAGGCUGACCGAAUGUAGUCUGUAUAAACUAGAUGGUUAAAGAUAAAGAAGCCUAUAUAUCAGAUGCAUAGACAAAGAAUAAAAUGGCAUCCAGAACUGGUCCCCACCUAUUCCCAAUCCUGGUUCCACAGCAGAAUACAUUCAUAGUUCAGGCAUUCUUCCUUGAGAUAGAUAUAAUGUAAGUGACCAAGUCUCUUGGACAAGUAUUGUCUCUGAUCAAUCCCUGCCAAACUCCUUUCCUUGGUUAACUCAAGUGGUUAGAUCUUACUCCCUGAACAGAAGGAAUAUGAGAGGUCAAUACAUGCCUAGACUAUUCAGUCCUCUGAUAUUGCUCCACACCCUUUCCCUCAAAAGCCAUGAGACCUUUCAAUGGUCCCAGUUCCUCUACCAGAACACCAGAGAUGCCUGCUUUACAUGGACUUAUAUAUUCCCAAGAAUCACUUGGAUAAAUGAGUGGUGCUGCUUUCCCGUGGUUGGGGAAAAGCUAGGAACCUGACAAUGCAGUGCUCAGAACCUGCUGACCGGUACUAGUUAUGCUGUCUUGCCAUAGUAGUGCAGUUCUUUAAAAUGUUGAUACUUGCUCUCUUAUCAAAGGUUGGUUUUUUUGUUUUUUUGUCAAGACAGGGUCUCACUAUGUCACCCAUACUGGAGUACAAUGGUGUAAUCUUGGCUUACUGCAACCUCCACCUUCUGGGCUCAAGCUGGCCUCUCACCUCAGCCUUCCAAGUAGCUGGGACCACACCCAGUCAAUUUUUUAUUUUUUAUUUUUUAAUUUAUUUUUAUUAUUACUUUUUUUGUAGAGAGAGGGUUUCGCCAUGUAGCCCAUGCUGGUCUUGAACUCCUGGGCUCAAGCUGUCUGCCCACCUGGACCUCCCAAAGUGCUGAGAUUACAGGCAUGAGCCACCGCACCCAGCCCAAAUAAAGUUUUAAGAAAUUACUUGGCCAGGCAUAGUGGGGCCUUUGUAGAAAAACAUAGCUUUUCUAUGAGAAGAUGAUCAAUAUUUUCUUUUCCUUUGAAUUUGGAAUUACCAUUUUGGAACUGUUGUCAACAAUGCAUAAUAAUAUAUCAGAAUGCUUCCUAGUAUAUUAUUGGAGAAAGAACAAACAAAAGUUUAAAUUGAUAUAAAAUGCAUAUAAUGGAACAAGCAACCCUGCAAAAAAAAAAAUAUAUAUAUAUAUAUACCAUCUGGGAAUUUCUGAUAAUAACAUUGAAAUCUGUUCACACAGUCUAAAAUUCUUUUGAUGUAUCGUAGUUUUGAAAAAAAGGUAACAGUUUACUAUAUAUAACAAAUAUAAGGAAAAUAUUAAAUUUUUUGAAAGAUACUAGUUUUUAUUUUUGUUCAUUUUUUAGAGACAGGGUCUCACUAUGUUGCCCAAGCUAGAGUGCAGCGGCCCGAUUAUAGCUCACUGCAGCCUCUAACUCCCGGACUCAAGGGAUCCUCCCACCUCAUCCUCCUAACUAGGACCACAGGCGCAUGUCACCACAUCUGGCUGAUUUUAAAAUUUUUUUGUGGAGACAGUCUUGCUGUGUUGCCCAGGCUGGUUAUGAACUCUUGGCCUCAGGCAGUCCUCAUGCCUCAGCCUCCCUAAGUGCUCGGAUUAUAGGCAUGCCACUGUGCCUGGCCAAAAAUACAGAUUUUUUAAUAGAUAUUACUAUGGCUCCUAUUCUUAAAGGAAAAAAUAUGACAUUUUAAGACUAUAUGCAAGGGAUAUUCCAAUAAUAUCUUUUUUAUUUAAAAAGCCACUAAUUAGAAUCAGAUUUCAUUAGGCAAGUGAAAUCCAGAUUUUACUAGCCAGAAACUGCCAGGUGUAGAAACAGCAAGAACAUUUUAGUCACUUCAUUGUUGACAUUUUUGACUAUCAUAGAUUAAGUAUCAAACACAAUAACAGUAUUUUGUUAUAUGAACCAAAUAUAUCUCUUUUUACGAGACAUAGUCUAGCUCUGCCAUCCAGGCUCAACUCCUGGGUUCAAGGGAUCCUCCUGCCCCAGCUUCCUGAGUACGUACCUGGGAGUACAAUUGCAUGCUGCCACACCCAGCUAUUUUUUUUAUUUUUGUGGAGAUGGCGUCUUGCUAUGUUGCCCAGGCUGGACUCCAACUCCUGACCUCAAGCAAUCAUCUCACCUUGGCCUCAAAAGUGCUAAGAUUACAGGCAUGAGCCACUGCAUCCAGCCUGAACCAAAUAUAUCUUUAUUAUAACUUAGGAGAGAAACGUUUUUGGCUGGUUAGUUUUACAGAAUUAAACCUAAUGGUUGUUCUAAUAGCAGUUCCAAUGAUUUGCAGAUUUGAGGAAGUAAAUUAUUUUCUUACAGUGUCCAUAAAAGUAACAAUGAAACUAUAUCCUACCAUAAUAAUCCUCUAUAGGUAAUAAAUUAUUUGCAUUUUAUAGGAGAGAAAAAUAUAUGUUAAAGUUUUUGAACAGUCACACAGGCAGGAAAUAAAUGGCAGUGAAUUUGAACUUGGACUUAUCUUGGACAAGCUCUUAACUGGUAUAUAUUUUGUCAAUCUUAUGUCGUGCACAAGAAUGAUGUUUUUAUAAAUGGAAAGAAUGAGUGUGGAAGUGUCUUCACUUGCCUAACAGAAAGGUUAUAUGUGGCUGGGCGCCGUGGCUAACGCCUGUAAUCCCAACAUUUUGGGAGGCUGAGGUGGGCAUAUCAUCUGAGGUCGGGAGUUCAAGAAUAGCCUGACCAACAUGGAGAAACCCCGUCUCUACUAAAAAUACAAAAUUAGCCAGUCAUAGUGGCACAUGCCUGUAAUCCCAGCUACUUGGAAGGCUGAGGCAGAAGAAUUGCUUGAACCCAGGAGGUGGAGGUUGUGGUGAGCCAAGAUCGCGCCAUUGCACUCCAUCCUGGGCAACAAGAGCGAAACUCCGUCUCAAAAAAAAAAAAAAAAAAAGUAAUACAUAAAUUUAAGUGACAUUUGUGGGUACUAAAUUACAAUAAUAUGUUCAGCUUUGCAUUUUUUUGCCUUUAAAAUUAAUUUCAAUUUUAGCGUGCCACUAAACGUAUUACUGUAAUAGUAUAUAAAUGUAUAAAGAUCAAUUUCUGUAUAUUCUAAUAGGAAUUGUAUAUAAGCAAAAAUGAAUUUUAGAAAUUAUCCUAUUAUUCAUGUAAUUAUGUCAUUCAUGUUAUUUAAAGGAAACCACAAUGCAGACAGGUUAAGUACCUAGUGUGAAGGUAUGUAACCAAUUAAUGGAGCUGUGCGACAUACAUCUGAGUAAUAAAGACUACAGAGAAAGUAUCUUGUUAGGUACUAUCUGAUACAAAGUUUAGAAACAUGUCAAACAAUUCUAUGUAUAGUUGGUGAAAGUGUAAUAACAUGGCUGAGACUUAAUACCAGAUGAAGUUCAGUGGUUUCAGGGGGAGGAAAUAAUUUUUAAAACGAUGUCGAUAACACUUCACAUUUAAAAUCAUCAUAAUAAUUCUAAUUCUAGAAUUGUGUCUAAUUCUAAUACUGUUUCUAGCUUUGCUUGAAUAAACAGAAAUGUAGUAGGGAAGAGACAGAAUGUUUAGCUUGCAGUAUCUAAUUACUCAUUUGGGUAUCUGGGAAGAUAGCUCUCCAUGGCCCCACUGUCACUGACCUAUAAUGCUUCUCCUGACGUCUUCGGUAAAAUCCAACAGAUUACAAAGAAACUGGAAUGCCUUGAAGAAAUAGAGCUUUUUGUGUGAUGUCAGAUUCAAUAGACCUCUAAUCCUUAGUAAAACAGUACAAAACAGUAGAAUAAUUUUUAGUGUUUUCUAAUAUCAACUGAGGUUUUAUUUGGGAGAUUAACCAGAGGUUUGCACAAAAACAAAAGUGAAGACCAUUAGUCUUUAAAGAAACUAAGACUCUAGGUUUGGAUCCCAUUUGUGGAGCCCUACAUUCCAAGUCAUCUAAUGUUCUUGUCUAGUUAGCUUGUAAAAGUCUAUACAAUGGAGGAAAACCCCUUUUUUCCCCUUAGUAUAAGUGUAUUAUAUGUUGAUAGAAAGGAUAGAAAGUUAAAUAACAGUUCAGUAAAUGUACUUCUAAAUGAAAUUUAAAA